ACACACUCGGAGCGUCUGCUAGGGCUGCAGCUCUGCGCGUCCAUCUCUGCGCUCUGCGCCAGCCUUCCCCACCGGGCCCAGCGAGUUUCCACCUGCAGGGCCGGUGCUCUCAGCUUUUGUUUUCUCUGGACACCUUCUUCUCUACCCCUGCUGUGCUGGCGCACACAUGCUGUCCUUGCUCCGGCUCUCCCUGCACCUACAGCUGUGGGAGCUCCCGGCAGCCUGGUACUGUGGGGUCGCUGCACGGAGCCACCAUGGCCUCUGACGUGGAGAGCUGUGACCUGCCGAGGCUUUGAUGUUGCUGCCCAGGGCUGGCCAGGACACUGGGGCCGCAGGAGAGGGGACUCACCGUGGUUCCCAGUGACCUGACAGCAGAGGAGCGUCAAGAACUGGAGAACAUCCGACGGAGAAAACAGGAGCUGCUGGCUGACAUUCAGAGGCUGAAGGAUGAGAUAGCAGAAGUAGCUAAUGAAAUUGAAAACCUGGGAUCCACAGAGGAAAGGAAAAACAUGCAGAGGAACAAACAGGUAGCCAUGGGCAGGAAAAAAUUUAAUAUGGACCCUAAAAAGGGGAUCCAGUUCUUAAUAGAGAACGACCUCCUGAAGAACACUUGUGAAGACAUUGCCCAGUUCUUAUAUAAAGGCGAAGGGCUCAACAAGACAGCCAUCGGCGACUACCUAGGGGAGAGAGAUGAGUUUAAUAUCCAGGUUCUUCAUGCAUUUGUGGAGCUGCAUGAGUUCACUGAUCUUAAUCUCGUCCAGGCACUACGGCAGUUCCUGUGGAGCUUCCGGCUACCCGGAGAGGCCCAGAAGAUCGACCGGAUGAUGGAGGCGUUUGCCCAGCGAUAUUGUCAGUGCAAUAAUGGCGUGUUCCAGUCCACGGAUACUUGUUACGUCCUCUCCUUUGCCAUCAUCAUGUUGAACACCAGUCUGCACAACCCCAAUGUCAAAGAUAAGCCCACUGUGGAGAGGUUCAUUGCCAUGAACCGAGGCAUCAAUGAUGGGGGAGACCUGCCGGAGGAGCUCCUCCGGAAUCUCUAUGAGAGCAUAAAAAAUGAACCCUUUAAAAUCCCAGAAGACGACGGGAAUGACCUCACUCACACUUUCUUCAAUCCAGACCGAGAAGGCUGGCUAUUGAAACUCGGUGGCAGGGUAAAGACUUGGAAGAGACGCUGGUUCAUUCUGACUGACAACUGCCUUUACUACUUUGAGUAUACCACGGAUAAGGAGCCCCGUGGAAUCAUCCCUUUAGAGAAUCUGAGUAUCCGGGAAGUGGAGGACUCCAAAAAACCAAACUGCUUUGAGCUUUAUAUCCCCGACAAUAAAGACCAAGUUAUCAAGGCCUGCAAGACCGAGGCUGACGGGCGGGUGGUGGAGGGGAACCACACUGUUUACCGGAUCUCAGCUCCGACGCCCGAGGAGAAGGAGGAGUGGAUUAAGUGCAUUAAGUAAGUGACUGCUGAGAAAGGGCAGUGCGCGCCUGGUGCAGCCCUCACCUCACCAGGUGUUGAUCAUCUUAGUGGUUAAACAUGCCGCCCGCAUCUCUUCUGUGCUCCAAGUUCUUAGGGAAGCUUCGUCCUGGUUCCCAGCUGACGGCUUCCCAGGAGGCCUUUGGAUUCUUGGCUAUUAUAGCAUAUGUAAGAGAGCACGUCCCAUCUGGGUUCCCCACGUGUCCUCAUAGACCCAAAAUAGGAAGAGGCGAGUGAGCUACCCACACAGAUGCCAUCUGCUCAACUGGUCUUUCUGUGUCUGACGAAGCCGCUCUCAUUCUCAUAGUGACAGCUCAGAGGAGAUAGUAGUCAUGUUCUGUAAUUUGUGAAUCCUGUGAGACACCAUUUUCCUAGCUACAGAUGAGGAAACUGAGGCCCAUAGAGGUUAAGAAAUUUGCUGGAAGUCACAUACCGUGAUCCAAGGUCCGGGAGGAGGGAGAAGCUUCCUCAGGGUUCCACAGCUAAGAAGUGGAGCUCCCAAGUCCAGGCCUCUGACUCCUACCUCUCGGCUCUGUUGGCUCCACUGGGCCACGCCAUGUAAGGUCUAUCACGGGGCUGGAAAUUUCCUCAUGUGACAAGUAUCUGGAAACAUGGCUUUCUAAAGUCAGUUGGCUUCUCUUGCUUAAUGUUCUUCCCUGGGACUUGGUCUGCCUGGCUCUCCCUCCAGUCCCUGUGCGAGGGUCAGCAGUGAGCAUUCUGACUUUGCCUUCUCUCAGUGAUGCUUUCUCCUCCCUCCAGUCCCUGUGCGAGGGUCAGCAGUGAGCAUUCUGACUUUGCCUUCUCUCAGUGAUCCUUUCUCCUAAGAGCACAGCCUUGCCCUCUCCCUCCUGGUGCUUCAUCCAUGAGAGUUCACCUAGCUGUUUUCCUGAGAAAGACUCCUCAGCUGCCUGUGUGACUUCACCUGGAAGACAGGGAGAAUGUGCCCACAGGUGACUGCGAAGGUCCCUGUAAGUCCUCUGUGUACUGUGUGACGGGCUUUCUCCCACCCAGGCUACAGCCCCGUUCCCGAGGGUGUGCAAUAUCCUCUAGCCUUUGUUUUAUCUUUUGGUAUUUCUACUCAGACCAGUGUAGGUUUUGGCCCAAGCUAAAUACCUUAAAACUGACUGAAGAUGGAGAUGAUGUGAUGAUGGAGGGAAAGGAAUAGAUGAUUUAUCCUCUCAAAAGUAAUCUGAAAAUUCAUGCAAUGAAAACAGACAGGAACCAGCUGGAGAGAGGAUGGAUUUGGCGCCAGGUCACGCUGCGCUGAGACUCCUCGCUCUGUCUCUCUGAGCGCAGUGCCUGGUAGGUGGGUAACCUACCUCUUCUGUGUGAUAGAGGUCAUUUCUGCCUCAUGGGGCUCUUUUGAGGAUUAAAUGAGAUUGUGUAGUGGGCAUGGGGUUUGGCAGCUUCCCUGGCAUGACAGCCAUCAUGGGAAGUGUGGCCCUGAGCGGGGGCCAGCCCACCCUCCAUUGAGCAGACGCGGUGCCACGGUGUUUUCAGAGUCCCCUACCAGUAAUGGCACCAGCCCUGUGUUCUGGGGAAGAAAACAGCAGUGUUGUGGGGGACCGGUAUCCUUUUUUUUAACAUACUGAAAAAAAAAUUUAUUGAAUCAUUAUGAAAUGUAUUUUUUAUAUAAGAUUUGAAGUAAGGGUUUAAGUUUGUUCUCAUGAAUGAAUAGCUGAUGGUCCGGACACCAUUUAUGGAUUCAUUGGCAUCGCCCCCACUGACUUCAUAUGCUCUCCUUAGAGUGUACCCAGCUCCCCCACCACGCUUCAUGCACCUGUUGCUCCACCGCGCCUCCCAGCGUGAGCGCCGCCCGCCCCUCCCCCUGUGGCAUCGUGGUGUCCUUUGACUGUGCUGGCUGGCGAGUUCCCUGUCCUCCCUCACUGGUCUUUCAAAACAGUUUUGGCUGGUUUUGUACAUGUGUCUUUCAUAUGGUUUUUACUUCUAUAGUCAGAAAAACUAAGCAUUUUUCAAAGUCACAUUUAGAAUCAUUCAAUCCUUUCAUGAGCGUGAGUGCCAAGUUCUCCUGUGGGCUUGCUGGACUCCUCUGCUCUGUCCCGGAGCGGGCUGGCCUCAGCCUCGGGAUCUGCAGACACCCCCUUUGGCACUCUGCAGGCACACUGUCCUCAAACCUUCUUGCACCCAGUGCGAGGUGGGACCAUUAGGAUUAUCCCCAUUUCACAGAUGAGGGACACUGAGGCACAGCAAAGUUGAGUAAGUUGUCCAAAACCCCACAGAGGUGGAGCUGGUCCUCAAACCUGAGCAGUGUGACUCAUGCAGCUGCACUGGUAACCACCGUGCAGCCUCAGCUGUCCUUGGCCCUAGAUACUCCUCCCAGUGGAAACAUUGGUGACAACAGGAGCAGGAAGAUGAUCUGGCUGGUGGAUGCCUCCUCCCCAGUAUUGCCAGAAAGGCUUUCGAGGUCAAGUUCAGGACGUGUUUUCCUCUCACGAAGUGCUUUUCCUGGAGUUCCCAGCACCCUCAGUUCUAGUGCCCCUGCGUGUGGGUGGUCCCAGCAUUCGGUUCUGUAGAAUCAGGUGUGUUCUCUAAUGCUGGGACUUUCUUCACGCUGUACCCAGAGGUACAGCAGUAGAACUGCGUGUCAGCGGUAACAGCGGCUGCCAUCGAGUGUGUCGGCUAGGCGCUGAGAUGUGCUCUUUGAAUAUGGGAUCUCUUUUUGACUCUCCGGAACCCAGGGAGGUGGAGGUGGGGCAUCUCCAGCUUGCAUGUGAGGAAGCGGGAGUUGAGAAGCAGCAGGCAGGGCCAGGCAGGGCCGGGCCUGGGGCCUGGUGUCCGACCGCAGCCCAGCCCCCCUCAUCGCCUGACACUCUGCCUCUGCACACAGGGCAGUGCCACACGCACCUCUCUGCAGAACCCCCCAGCUUACCCGAAAGGGUUGGCCUACCCAGGAAGCCAAGGGAGAUUCACCCCAACACCUCCAAACAUGAAAGCAGGUGUCCCGGCCGCCAGAUUCCCUCGUGAAAGCACUUCAGGUGGUCAGACCGCUUCCCAGUGAGAUCCCAUCGGGACAUGUUUCUAGUGCUCUUCAGUUCCUAGCAUUCCCCGGGGAGCUGCGGAAGCAUUUUCUCAUGGACACACUGUCUCUUGUGAAUAGGUUCCAGGUCAGCCCAGGAGAGCCAUAGCAGCUGCUGGUGCCACCGUUCAGCAGGGGUGAGUGCCCUGCCUGCAGUCAGGAGGCUUGUGCCCGAGCUCUGGAACAAAUCAUCACUUAGGAUACAGCUUCCCUGGAAAGAAAUUAAGUGUCAGGACUUUUAGACCAUAAGUUGCUUGAAAGUCGAGAAUGGCAGACAUAGGGUUGUGGUGUUGCCAGUCCACUGCAGGUGCUCCAGCCCGCGGCGCGGCCUGCGCUGCUGUCUUUGAGGCUGUAGCACAAGCAUGAGCUCGGGCCCCCUCCCUGUGCACCGGAGACCCAGCCAGGUCCAGCCGGUCUGUCCAUGGUGCCCCACCAGCAGCAUCGUGCUGGGCAGUGCCGCCUGCAGAGUCAUGGAGCCUUAGUUACUGAGCAGGUGCACGUGGGGGGCUUGGAAGGCCCCACUGCAUUACCAUGCCAGCUAUCACACACCCCGUGCCAGAGGACUGCAUGUGACACGGCUUGAUUACGUGGCACUCGCUGCUGCAAAGCAAAGUCAGAUGUCAUCAUGGAAACUCAAGCACCAGUCUUUUUCUCUGAAUUGGAAUAUAGCUGUAAGAAUGUGGUAUGAUUCUGUUCCUAAAUGUGAAUUGAUUAUUAUGUUGAAACAGGUAAAAACCCCAAAAUUUUCUUGUCACGUGUUCCUGUGUCUCUUUCGAAGUGUGUCACCUUAGGUCACUGUGUGGACACAGCAAGGGUGGAGGACGCUAACUUGGCCUUUGCAGUGAUGGUGGGGUGGGACAGGUGUUCUGGGGCACGAGGGGCCCCUGAGAAUCCCCUGCCUGGGUGUGUUUCUUCUGAUUCUGUCCCUCACGUCUCUGUUUUCUCCCUUUUCUGUGCUCCAGAGCAGCCAUCAGCAGGGACCCUUUCUACGAAAUGCUCGCAGCACGGAAAAAGAAGGUCUCCUCCACGAAGCGACACUGAGCGUGCAGCCAAGGGCGUUGGUCUGCGGGGGCCUUGGAGCUCCUGCUCUUCUCCCGCACCUCCAUGGAUGCACUGCUGCCGAGCAGAGCGUCCUCUGCCAGGCCCCGCCCUGGAUUCCUAGAGACUAGCUUCAGCUUUUGCUAUUUUUUUUAAGUGGGAGAAGGGUGGGCAGUUAUCACUGGGGAAGAGAGGACCGGCCACCUGUCCAGCAUGGGCUCCAGAGCCUUCCUCUCUCACAGGGCAGAGCUCUUGUCGGCAGGGCAGCCUCCUGGCCAGUUUCUCUGCUCAGUGUUCUGGUAGCAGAGCUCAGAGCCAACUGUUUACCUCUUGGUUGUCCCCGUGAAGAAGCCUUCAAACCCUGCACCAUAAAUACAUGUGUCCAUAUAUUAUUAUAUGUUAAGAGAAAAAGGUGGAAAGGAAGAGAAGCCACAUACUAUAAAGAUCUAUUUUUUUUUUUUUAAGAGAGAACGUAGGGCUGUUCAGGUGCAUUCUGCCCUGGCUGCGCUGGGGAGCUUCUCCCUGGAGAAGAGCACCUGGGGCUGCGGCCAAGGGGCAUCAGCCUGGGCCCGCGGCAGGGCCUGGCCUGCCUCUCCUGUGCUGUGGGAGCUCGCUGCCUGGUGCUUGUCUGGGCGAGAUGGACAGGUGAGGUCGAGGACGCAGAGGGCAGAGGCCCAGUGGAGCCUCAGACGGCACAGUCAGAGUCGGGGGCCUGCCCUGGCCGGGGUCGCAGUCGGCAGCAGCGUGCAGUCCGGCAUCUCCCGCGGAUGCUUUUCCAUCCCAAGUGCCUGCGGAGCGCCGAGGAGAGGAGAGAGCUGACUGGACGCUUACGUUAUUUUCCUCCUUCAGAAUCCAAGUUCUUGUUGGGCUUUAAAGUAGAAAGUCAGCAUUUUCCUUGAGCUAAAUACCUAAUAACCAAAACUGUGAGGAAGGUUAUCGGGACAGAGGUUCCGGAUAACCUGUUUCAUUUUGGGUUUUCUUCCUCUUCCCCAGACUCCAGUCCUCGUUCUAGAGGAAGGAGUAGGACUUCCCCGAUCCCCGUAGGGCUUCAGCUUUUUCUGCCUCAAAACCAGCCCUAACUGGACUACUCUGGAUGCAUUUUGUGGUGGGCCCCCUAGAGGGGAAGAUGGGCCUUUAUCUGCUCCGUGGGGUGCACUGGAGUGAGGGGGGUGGCCGGGCUGCCUCUCGCAUCUCUGUCUUCCCCUGCAGGCGCUGUGUGAGCUGGCCCUGCCCCUCCUCAUUACAGUAUGAAGGGAGCCGUGACACGCAGCAUUUUCCUGCCGUUCUCUCAGGGACUCUCAGGGCAGCUCCUGCCACUCCGCCAGGGCCAGCAUGCCAGUCCAGGCAGAGCAGGUGGCUGGCUGUCUGGCCGUCUCGCCCCGCCCCUCCACAGGACCCUGGACCAGGGCGGUGCAGGGCGCAGCCCUGAGGAGGCAGGUGGAGGAGCUGCGGGUUUUCACAGGGCCGCGUCGCCACGGCUCCUCUGAUCCUUUAGGGUUGGCGAGCAUCUCUGGAAAUAGCUUUUGCAGAGGAGUGGUGGGAGGAAUAGAGGGGGACAGUCUGUCACCUCCCUCCCCGCCACUUUGUGUAGAUCCUACCUGGAGGGAAUGGCUUUAGGCACUUUUGUGCCAGAGCUUGUGAGGGUGACAGAAGAGGGUCCAGGCUGGAAACCUGAACUUUCUGGGUGGGAGAACCAGGUGGUGCCUGCCGAGGUCUGGGCGUGUUUGGGCCGGUGCUGGAGCCUGUCCAGCUGGCCCGGGCCCUGGCCUGGUUCUCAAGUGUUUCCUAGACAGAGAGGCACCUGGGUCAGUAUUAGUCUAUUUAUCAGAGGUGUAAAUAAUCUAUGUAUAGUUUUUCUCCUUUUAGAUUAUUUUGUAUUUGUUUAAAAGAAGUUUUGUCAAAAUACAAAAAUAUAAAGAAAUGACUGAAAGUUGUUGACAGGGUUUUUAAGAAAUAAUUAUUCUAAUUGUUUUUGUUUGUUUGUUUUUGCCUUGUAAACUAGCGCCAAGGAACUGCAGCAAAUAAACUCCAACUCUGCCCAAGCCA